UCUCUCAUCGUCUGGGCGAGCGGGGCGGCUCGUGGUGUUUCUAACCCAGUUCGUGGAUUCAAAGGUGGCUCCGCGCCGAGCGCGGCCGGCGACUUGUAGGACCUCAGCCCUGGCCGCGGCCGCCGCGCACGCCCUCGGAAGACUCGGCGGGGUGGGGGCGCGGGGGUCUCCGUGUGCGCCGCGGGAGGGCCGAAGGCUGAUUUGGAAGGGCGUCCCCGGAGAACCAGUGUGGGAUUUACUGUGAACAGCAUGGAGGAGAAUGACCCCAAGCCUGGCGAAGCAGCGGCGGCGGUGGAGGGACAGCGGCAGCCGGAAUCCAGCCCCGGCGGCGGCUCGGGCGGCGGCGGCGGUAGCAGCCCGGGCGAAGCGGACACCGGGCGCCGGCGGGCUCUGAUGCUGCCCGCGGUCCUGCAGGCGCCCGGCAACCACCAGCACCCGCACCGCAUCACCAACUUCUUCAUCGACAACAUCCUGCGGCCCGAGUUCGGCCGGCGAAAGGACGCGGGGACCUGCUGUGCGGGCGCGGGAGGAGGAAGGGGCGGCGGAGCCGGCGGCGAAGGCGGCGCGAGCGGUGCGGAGGGAGGCGGCGGCGCGGGCGGCUCGGAGCAGCUCUUGGGCUCGGGCUCCCGAGAGCCCCGGCAGAACCCGCCAUGUGCGCCCGGCGCGGGCGGGCCGCUCCCAGCCGCCGGCAGCGACUCUCCGGGUGACGGGGAAGGCGGCUCCAAGACGCUCUCGCUGCACGGUGGCGCCAAGAAAGGCGGCGACCCCGGCGGCCCCCUGGACGGGUCGCUCAAGGCCCGCGGCUUGGGCGGCGGCGACCUGUCGGUGAGCUCGGACUCGGACAGCUCGCAAGCCGGCGCCAACCUGGGCGCGCAGCCCAUGCUCUGGCCGGCGUGGGUCUACUGUACGCGCUACUCGGACCGGCCUUCUUCAGGUCCCAGGUCUCGAAAACCAAAGAAGAAGAACCCGAACAAAGAGGACAAGCGGCCGCGCACGGCCUUUACCGCCGAGCAGCUGCAGAGGCUCAAGGCCGAGUUCCAGACCAACAGGUACCUGACGGAGCAGCGGCGCCAGAGCCUGGCGCAGGAGCUGAGCCUCAACGAGUCACAGAUCAAGAUUUGGUUCCAGAACAAGCGCGCCAAGAUCAAGAAGGCCACGGGCAACAAGAACACGCUGGCCGUGCACCUCAUGGCACAGGGCUUGUACAACCACUCCACCACAGCCAAGGAGGGCAAGUCGGACAGCGAGUAGGGCGGGGGGCAUGGAGGCCAGGUCUCAGUCCGCGCUAAACAAUGCAAUAAUUUAAAAUCAUAAAGGGCCAGUGUAUAAAGAUUAUACCAGCAUUAAUAGUGAAAAUAUUGUGUAUUAGCUAAGGUUCUGAAAUAUUCUAUGUAUAUAUCAUUUACAGGUGGUAUAAAAUCCAAAAUAUCUGACUAUAAAAUAUUUUUUUGAGUUUUUUGUGUUUAUGAGAUUAUGCUAAUUUUAUGGGUUUUUUUCUUUUUUGCGAAGGGGGCUGCUUAGGGUUUCACCUUUUUUUAAUCCCCUAAGCUCCAUUAUAUGACAUUGGACACUUUUUUAUUAUUCCAAAAGAAGAAAAAAUUAAAACAACUUGCUGAAGUCCAAAGAUUUUUUAUUGCUGCAUUUCACACAACUGUGAACCGAAUAAAUAGCUCCUAUUUGGUCUAUGACUUCUGCCACUUUGUUUGUGUUGGCUUGGUGAGGACAGCAGGAGGGGCCCACACCUCAAGCCUGGACCAGCCACCUCAAGGCCUUGGGGAGCUUAGGGGACCUGGUGGGAGAGAGGGGACUUCCAGGGUCCUUGGGCCAGUUCUGGGAUUUGGCCCUGGGAAGCAGCCCAGCGUACCCCAGGCCUGCUCUGGGAAGUCGGCUCCAUGCUCACCAGCAGCCGCCCAGGCCCGCAGCCUCACCCGGCUCCCUCUCCUCACCCUCCUGCACCUAACUCCCUCCUCCUUCUCCUUUUUCCUCCUCUUCCUCCUUCCUCCUUCCUCCUGCUCCUCCUUUCUUCUUCUUUUUCUUCUCCUCCUCCUCCUUCCUUCCUCCUCCUCCUUCUCUUUCCUCCUCCUCCUCACCAAGGGCCCAACCGUGUGCAUACAUCGUCUGCGUCUGUGGUCUGUGUCGCUGUCCCCAGUCCCACCGCAGUCCUGCCGCAGGCCUAACCCUCCUGCCCUGGGCACUGCCUCCAUGCAGAAGCGCUUCGAGGUUCUGGGGCUAAAGGCCUGGGGUGUGUGGCCUAAAGCCCAAGAGCGGUGGGGCGACCCUCCUUUUGGCUUGGCCCCAGGAAUUUCCUGUGACUCCACCAGCCAUCAUGGGUGCCAGCCAGGGUCCCAGAAAUGAGGCCAUGGCUCACUGUUUCUGGGCGGGCAGAAGGCUCUGUAGAGGGAGAUGGCAUCAUCUAUCUUCCUUUCCUUUUUCUUUUCUUCCCUAUUUUUUUCUUUUUUUCCUUUAUUUUUUUCUUUUCUUGGAGUGGCUGCUUCUGCUAUAGAGAACAUUCUUCCAAGAUAAAUAUGUGUGUUUACACAUAUGUCUGCAUGCAUGUGAACACACACACACACACACACACACCAGGCGUGUUUGAGUCCACAGUUCUGAAACAUGUGGCUACCUUGUCUUUCAAAAGAACUCAGAAUCCUCCAGGAUCUAGAAGAAGGAAGAAAGUGUGUAAAUAAUCAUUUCUUAUCAUCACUUUUUGUCUUUUCUUGUUUUUUAAAAUAUACAUUUUAUUUUUGAAGGUGUGGUACAGUGUAAAUUAAAUAUAUUCAAUAUAUUUCCCACCAAGUACCUAUAUAUGUAUAUAAACAAACACAUUAUCUAUAUAUAACGCCACACUGUCUUCUGUUUAGUGUAUGGGGAAAGACCAAUCCAACUGUCCAUCUGUGGCUGGGACAGCCCAGGGGGUGUGCCCACGGCUGACCCAGGGGUGUGCACACGGCUGAGCUGGGAGUCCCGCUGGUCUCCCUGAGGACUGAGGGUGAACUUCGCUCUUUGCCUUAAACCUCUUUAUUUCAUUGCAGUAAUAGUUUUACGUUGUACAUAAUAGUGUAAACCUUUUUAAAAAGGAAAGUAUAAAAACAAAAGUUGUAAUUUAAAAGUCUGAAUAACCAUCUGCUGCUUAGGAAACUCAAUGAAAUGACAUGCCUUUUUAGCAGGAAGCAAAGUUGGUUUCUGUUUUUUGUUUUCUUUGUUGUUUUAGUUUAUAAAACAUGUGCAUUUUACAGUUCCAGUAUCAAAUAUUUAUAAUCUUAUGAGAAAUGAAUGAAUGUUUCUAUUUACAACUGUGCUUAUCAAAAUUGUGAACACCCCCACCCCCGCAUUUUUGUGUGUUGAAAUUCUUGAAGGUUACAUUAAAUAAAACAAAAUCUCUUUAUUAUAAAAUA